ACUUCCGGUAGGAGAGUCCCAAACGGCCAGCGGCUGGGAAUUUGCGGUAUCGCGGGGGGGUGGGAAAUUUCCCUUGGUGCGUGCUCCUUCUGAUGUCAGCCUUCAAAACGUUUGUGGGACUCCCCUUUGAUUUGAGUCUCUGCUGCUAGCAGCUGCUUCCCUGACCUCUAAAACCAGGAAAGACCAUAGGUUCUCUAAGUGAGCAGCCGCCGUUUGCUGCUCUUAGAAAACUCACAGAAGUGAAGAGUGUUUCUUUCCUGACUUAUUCCUGUUCCCCUAGGCAGGCGUGCUAGGGGUUAGGAGUUCUGCCGUGAUUCUUCUUCAUUCAUUUAUUAAUCUAUUCAUUCACGUAUUCAUUCAUUGGCUUAUGCAUUUAUGUACUCAUUGAUUGAUUGAUCGAUUGCAGACGAGGUCGGGCUGUGUUGCCCAGGGGGACUCAAUUUCCUGGGCUCAAGCGAUCUUCCUGCCUCGACUUCCCAAAGUGGUGGGAUUGCAGGCUCAGCCACCGCGCCCGGCCCCUGUCGUGAUUCUUAGUUCUGAAAAGAAUUGAUUGGGAGACGAGCCAUGGAAGGCCUGGAGCCACAGAGUUCAGUUAUGUGAUUAAUAAUAACACAUAAUAAUAACACAUAGCACCCCUCUCCAUUUUGCCAAGCAUUAGGUAUGUUCGUGGAUCCCAGAUCGAAGUCCACGCAUAAGCCAAUUCGCUGUGUAAUUGUUUUCAAUUCCACUUUCCAUGGUUAGGUUCUAGCAUUGAAAAGAAAAGCUUCACAGCCUGGCAUGAAACGAAACUGAAUGUCCUUGAAACCAGUUGACGGAGGAGCAAGCUUAAAAUUUUUUUAGACUCUGACUUCAGUCAGAUGGUUGGAUUUUAACCUUGGCAACGUGGCCUUUUAACAUGCCAAACUCUUGAGUUAACCUGUACAAGGAGAAUGUAUGACUUACGUCCUCCCAGUGCUAUGGUUUAAAGACCCUUUAAGACUUAGAUGCAGGAUAAUAUGCUCCAACGUUACAACAUUAAAGGCAAGUUUCAACCUCCUAUGUAGAGGAAAAAGAAUGUACUGACCCUAUGCAAACUUAACUUUCAUGACUAUCAGUUGGACCAUAAAUGUGAAUAAUUUUGUGUUUGUGUAAGUAAUGGCUUAAAAGGACAUUUUUAGUCCUAGCUUCAUUAUCACAAAACAAACUUUAGAUUCCGUAACAGCUUCUUCAAUUGUUAGACAUGGAUGUAAACCACAUUCUGCUUUUUUUUUUUUUUUCUGGCUUUCGGAUUUCUAAGAAACCAUUUCUGAAAAGAACAAAGCAUUUUUGUAUGAAGAUGCAGACAUUUGGCUGGGCGCUGGGGCUCAUGCUUGUAAUCCCAGCACUUUGGGAGGCUGAGGCGGGUGGAUCACGAAGUCAAGAGAUGGAGACCAUCCUGGCCAACAUGGUGAAACCCUGUCUCUACUAAAAAUACAAAAAUUAGCCGGGUGUGGUGGCACGCGCCUGUAAUCCUAGCUACUCAGGAGGCUGAGGCAGGAGAAUUGCUUGAACCUGGGAGGCAGAGGUUGCAGGGAGCAGAGAUCACACCAGGGCACUUCAGCCUGGCGACAGAGUGAGACUCCGUCUAAAAAAAUAAAAAUAAAAAUAAAAUAAAGAAAAUGCAGAGAUUUGAAGCAAAAAAAACUAUAGAUUUCUUAAACAUUUUUAUGAUAUUUUAGAGACAGUAAGUUUGAAUUAUACUUCUACUUUUAACUAAGUGGAAUGAAUGUAUUUAUUUGAACAUGGCUCUUGAUAUUUUUAUUGGUUUUGUUUCUUUGAAAUUUCAGAAAACUUUAGUGUUGAAGUUUUCAGUUCGUUAAAAUUUACUUUUAACUUACUUUUAACACCUUUCUUAUGAACAAUUUACCUGACAAUGAGACUGUUCUAAUAUUUUAAAAAUAUUUUUUCAUAUUUAAAAGUUUUGUUUGCUGAUUUGGAAAUCUAAAAUUUUUACAAACUGGAGGGAAAGAAAAAUAGCCACAAUUAUCAAAAGUAAUAUGAUUGAUUAACAGAAUAUAGUUGUGUAUUAUCUAAACAGAUAUCAUGCUGAUGUACCUAUCGAUCUGUUAGAAAAAAUACUUUCAAUUACAUUAGGAGAGGCACGGUGGCUCAUGCCUGUGAUGCUAGCAGUUUGGGAGGCCAAGGCAGGUGGAUUACUUGAGCCCAGGAAUUUUAGAUCAACCCAGACAACAUGGAGAAAUCCUGUCUCUCCAAAAAAAUACAAAAGUUAGCUGGACAUGGUGGUGCACAUGUGUAGUCCCGACUAAUGAGGUGGCUGAGGCAAGAGGCUCAUUUGAGCCAAGGAGGUCAAGACUGCAGUGGGCUAAGAUCGUGCAUCUGGACUCCAGCCUGGGUGACAGUGAGACCCUGUCUGAACCAAAAAAAAAAAAAAAAAAAAAAAAAAGGAUUGUAACUAAUUUUCUUAAGUGUUCAUUGGAAAUAACUUCCUUUAAUUAAAUUGGAAUCCCAGUAAAAUCUCUAUCCAGUUCAACAAAAUAUUUUAAAGAGUUCAAGGAAGAAAAAUGUCAAACAACUCGGGAAUUCAAAAAAUAAAACUAUAAGAUGUUUUUAAAAGGAACUAUUACAAACUAACUUCAGAUAAUACUUGGAAGAGCUAGCUGUAGCUGUAAUUGAAUUCAAUUUAUUACUUAUACAACUCUGAUCAAUUUGUCCAUUGCUUUUUUUAAACGGAGUCUCACUCUGUCACCUAGGCUGGAGUGCAGUUGUGUGAUCUCAGCUCACUGCAACCUCUGCCUCCCGGGUUCAAGCAGUUCUCCUGCCUCAGUCUCUUGAGUAGCUGGGAUUACAGGCAUGCACCACCAUGCCCAGUUAAUUUUUGUAUUUUUAGUAGAGAUGGGGUUUCACCAUGUUGGUCAGGCUGGUCUUGAACUCCUGACCUCGUGAUCCACCUGCCUUGGCCUCCCAAAGUGCUGGAAGCCACCAUUUUUUAACUUUCCUCAACCUUUAAGGUAAUGCCCAUUGUGAUUUUAGUUUAGUUGAUCAGUCUCCAGAUUAGGUGUGACUGAUAGAUUUCCCGUCAGAAAAUUCUACCUGCCAUAUGGUCUGAAAUCAAUAUGAUCGCCUUCUGUAAAUAUCUAUUGAGAGACCAACAAUUUUUGAUGCUGUGGGAAGGAUACGAGCAAGAUAAAGCAGCGAGGGAUUUAAGUCUGGCAACAGUUGGACUGCUGGAUUUUCAGAGAAGUGUUCCCCAAAGCAAAUUAUAGUGCUAAUUUCCAAUGUUCCAUAAGCGUGGCAAGAAAAAUGGGAAGUUCUCGAUUGUGACUGCUUUAGGUAAACAAGAAGCAGAAAGGAAGUUUGAAACUUUGUUAAAGCACCUGUCACAUCCUCCAUCAUUUACAACUGUCAGAGUGAAUACACAUUUAGCCUCAGUACAACAUGUGAAAAAUCUGUUACUUGAUGAACUUCAGAAGCAGUUUAAUGGAUUAAGUGUUCCUAUUCUUCAACAUCCAGACCUUCAAGAUGUGUUACUUAUUCCUGUUAUUGGACCCAGAAAGAAUAUUAAAAAACAACAGUGUGAAGCCAUUGUUGGAGCCCAGUGUGGCAAUGCAGUUUUAAGAGGAGCCCAUGUCUAUGCCCCAGGAAUUGUGUCAGCAUCACAAUUUAUGAAAGCUGGAGAUGUUAUUUCUGUAUACUCUGAUAUUAAAGGAAAAUGUAAGAAAGGAGCCAAAGAAUUUGAUGGAACAAAAGUAUUUCUUGGAAAUGGGAUUUCUGAACUAAGCCGCAAAGAAAUCUUCAGUGGAUUACCUGAACUGAAGUAUGUCAUCAGAGGCAUGGGCAUAAGAAUGACAGAACCAGUAUAUCUCAGCCCUUCAUUUGACAGUGUACUGCCCCGUUACUUAUUUUUACAAAAUUUGCCAUCUGCCUUAGUAAGUCAUGUACUAAAUCCUCAACCUGGAGAGAAGAUUCUAGACUUGUGUGCAGCACCUGGAGGGAAAACAACACACAUUGCAGCACUAAUGCAUGAUCAGGGAGAAGUUAUAGCACUGGAUAAAAUCUUCAACAAAGUAGAAAAAAUCAAACAGAAUGCCUUAUUGUUAGGGCUGAAUUCCAUCAGGGCAUUUUGUUUUGAUGGAACAAAGGCGGUUAAACUUGAUAUGGUGGAGGACACAGAAGGAGAACCUCCAUUUCUACCAGAAUCCUUUGACCGAAUUCUUCUGGAUGCACCCUGUAGUGGAAUGGGACAGAGACCAAACAUGGCCUGUACUUGGUCUGUGAAGGAAGUGGCAUCAUAUCAGCCAUUACAGCGAAAACUCUUCACUGCAGCGGUUCAGCUGCUGAAGCCAGAGGGUGUGCUGGUUUAUAGCACGUGCACUAUAACACUGGCCGAAAAUGAAGAACAGGUUGCCUGGGCCCUGACAAAAUUUCCUUGCCUUCAGCUUCAGCCCCAGGAACCGCAGAUUGGAGGAGAAGGAAUGAGGGGAGCUGGGCUCUCAUGUGAACAGUUGAAACAGCUGCAGCGAUUUGAUCCAUCGGCUGUGCCAUUACCGGACACUGACAUGGACUCUCUUAGAGAGGCCAGAAGAGAAGACAUGUUGCGUCUGGCUAAUAAGGACUCUAUAGGUUUUUUUAUUGCAAAAUUUGUAAAAUGCAAAAGCACAUAGGAGAGGGAUGGAUGCUCAGAAAUGAAAAUUCCAAACAUUUGCUGUCUGUGGUUUUUUUUUUUUUAACCAAAGUGUUGUCAGGCCAACUGAAUGAUGAUGUGGUUGCUAUGGAAACAGAAAAGGCUGCCAGCUGUUUUACCAGGGAUCCAGAGACAUAGAGGAAGUAGGGGGUGGUAUGAGAUUAUAUUUUCUGUUUUUAAAAGAUUUUUUUUUUUUAUGUAUUUAGUAGAGUAUAAAGAAAAGCAGAUGCCUAUAGAUGUCUGGAGCAUAUUUUCAUUUGUGAUCUAAUGUUUUAAUUUGUAAAGUGUACAAGUCAUUUUUAAUGUUAAAAAUUAGUGAAUCUAACAAAAGGAAUAAAUUAGCAAUAUUUGA